CUCUCCCUCCCUCCCAGCUCCUGCACCAGGAAACGGCCCGGAUCCCGGCAGCGGCCUGACCCGUGAGAUCCCUAACCUGGCAGGCGGGCGGGGUUGGAGACUGGCUGAGGUGGGGGGCUCCACGCUGGCCAGGAGGAUGAAAGGCCCCAGCUGGGGGCUCCUUGCCACCAGUGCUGUGUCUUAAGAGCUGCCAUCCCGGCUGGCCGCCCGGAUGGCGACCCCAGCCUCGGCCCCAGACACACGGGCUCUGGUGGCAGACUUUGUAGGUUAUAAGCUGAGGCAGAAGGGUUAUGUCUGUGGAGCUGGCCCCGGGGAGGGCCCAGCAGCUGACCCGCUGCACCAAGCCAUGCGGGCAGCUGGAGAUGAGUUCGAGACCCGCUUCCGGCGCACCUUCUCUGAUCUGGCGGCUCAGCUGCAUGUGACCCCAGGCUCAGCCCAACAACGCUUCACCCAGGUCUCCGAUGAACUUUUUCAAGGGGGCCCCAACUGGGGCCGCCUUGUAGCCUUCUUUGUCUUUGGGGCUGCACUGUGUGCUGAGAGUGUCAACAAGGAGAUGGAACCACUGGUGGGACAAGUGCAGGAGUGGAUGGUGGCCUACCUGGAGACGCAGCUGGCUGACUGGAUCCACAGCAGUGGGGGCUGGUUAUCCCAGAUCACUGAAGCUGAGAUGGCUGAUGAAGUAAUUUGCAGUGAAAUUUUAAGCGACUGUGACUCUGCUGCAAGUUCCCCAGAUCUUGAGGAGCUGGAAGCUAUCAAAGCUCGAGUCAGGGAGAUGGAGGAAGAAGCUGAGAAGCUAAAGGAGCUACAGAACGAGGUAGAGAAGCAGAUGAAUAUGAGUCCACCUCCAGGCAAUGCUGGCCCGGUGAUCAUGUCCAUUGAGGAGAAGAUGGAGGCUGAUGCCCGUUCCAUCUAUGUUGGCAAUGUGGACUAUGGUGCAACAGCAGAAGAGCUGGAAGCUCACUUUCAUGGCUGUGGUUCAGUCAACCGUGUUACCAUACUGUGUGACAAAUUUAGUGGCCAUCCCAAAGGGUUUGCGUAUAUAGAGUUCUCAGACAAAGAGUCAGUGAGGACUUCCUUGGCCUUAGAUGAGUCCCUAUUUAGAGGAAGGCAAAUCAAGGUGAUCCCAAAACGAACCAACAGACCAGGCAUCAGCACAACAGACCGGGGUUUUCCACGAGCCCGCUACCGCGCCCGGACCACCAACUACAACAGCUCCCGCUCUCGAUUCUACAGUGGUUUUAACAGCAGGCCCCGGGGUCGCGUCUACAGGUCAGGAUAGAUGGGCUGCUCCUCUUUCCCCCGCCUCCCGUGAGCCCCGUAUGCUUCCUCCUCUCUGGUCUGAGGAACCUCCCUCCCCCCACCCCUCCCCGUGGUCUUCAGGAACUUUGUCUCCUGCCUGUGCAGGUUGAGGAAGGUAGUUGCAGGCCAGGCCAGAAGGCCAGCCUCAUCAUCUUUUCUGCAGUAGAAAUUGGUGAUAAGGGCUGCAUCCCUCCCUUGGUUCAAAGAGGCUUCCACCCCCAGCCUUUUUUUUCUUGGGAGUUGGUGGCAUUUGAAGGUGUUUGCGGACAAAACUGGGAGGAACAGGGCCUCCAGGCAGUGAAAGCACUGCUUGGACAUUUGUUACUUUUUUCGGAGUUAGGGAGGGAUUGAAGACUGAACCUCCCUUGGAAGAAUACCAGAGGCUAGCUAGUUGAUCCUCCCCAACAGCCUUGUGGGAGGAUUUUGAGAUACUUAUUCUUUAUUUGAGCCAGUCUUGCAAGGUUAACUUCUCACUGGGCCUAGUGUGGUGCCCAGGUUUUUGCCUUGCUUCACUUCUGUCUCUACAUUUAAAUAGACGGGUUAGGCAUAUAAACCUUGGCUUUUCAUAAGCUCUACCUGCCUAUCCCCAGGAGUUAGGGAGGAUCUAUUUGUGAUGGCCUAGGGUUUAAGAGCUGUGGAGGACUGAAAACUGGAUAAAAAGGGGGUCCUUUUCCUUGCCCCUGUCUCUCACUCAGAUGCGCUUCUUUUUCGCCACUGUUUGGCAGUUUUCUGUUAAGCCCCCCUCCCCCUGCCCCAGUUCUCCAGGUGCGUUACUAUUUCUGGGAUCAUGGGGUCAGUUUUAGGACACUUGAACACUUCUUUUCCCCCCUUCCCUUCACAGUAACUGGGGCAGGGGCCUACGGGGAGGGGCUUGUACUGAACUAUCUAGUGAUCACGUUAACACCUAACUCUCCUUCUUUCUUCCAGGGGCCGGGCUAGAGCGACAUCAUGGUAUUCCCCUUACUAAAAAAAGUGUGUAUUAGGAGGAGAGAGAGGAAAAAAAGAGGAAAGAAGGAAAAAAAAAAGAAUUAAAAAAAAAAAAAAGAAAAACAGAAGAUGACCUUGAUGGAAAAAAAAUAUUUUUUAAAAAAAAGAUAUACUGUGGAAGGGGGGAGAAUCCCAUAACUAACUGCUGAGGAGGGACCUGCUUUGGGGAGUAGGGGAAGGCCCAGGGAGUGGGGCAGGGGGCUGCUUAUUCACUCUGGGGAUUCGCCAUGGACACGUCUCAACUGCGCAAGCUGCUGCCCAUGUUUCCCUGCCCCACUUCACCCCCUUGGGGGCUGCUCAAGGGUAGGUGGGCGUGGGUGGUAGGAGGUUUUUUUUUUUACCCAGGGCUCUGGAAGGACACCAAACUGUUCUGCUUGUUACCUUCCCUCCGUCUUCUCCUCGCCUUUCACAGUCCCCUCCUGCCUGCUCCUGUCCAGCCAGGUCUACCACCCACCCCACCCCUCUUCUCCGGCUCCCUGCCCCUCCAGAUUGCCUGGUGAUCUAUUUUGUUUCCUUUUGUGUUUCUUUUUCUGUUUUGAGUGUCUUUCUUUGCAGGUUUCUGUAGCCGGAAGAUCUCCGUUCCGCUCCCAGCGGCUCCAGUGUAAAUUCCCCUUCCCCCUGGGGAAAUGCACUACCUUGUUUUGGGGGGUUUAGGGGUGUUUUUGUUUUUCAGUUGUUUUGUUUUUUUGUUUUUUUUUUUUUUCCUUUGCCUUUUUUCCCUUUUAUUUGGAGGGAAUGGGAGGAAGUGGGAACAGGGAGGUGGGAGGUGGAUUUUGUUUAUUUUUUUAGCUCAUUUCCAGGGGUGGGAAUUUUUUUUUAAUAUGUGUCAUGAAUAAAGUUGUUUUUGAAAAUAAAAA